GUCGAGCCAGGACGGUGACAGCGUUUAACAAAGCUUAGAGAAACCUCCAGGAGACUGCUAUCAUGGCAGAGAAGCCCAAGCUCCACUACUUCAAUGCACGGGGCAGAAUGGAGUCCACCCGGUGGCUCCUGGCUGCAGCUGGAGUAGAGUUUGAAGAGAAAUUUAUAAAAUCUGCAGAAGAUUUGGACAAGUUAAGAAAUGAUGGAUAUUUGAUGUUCCAGCAAGUGCCAAUGGUUGAGAUUGAUGGGAUGAAGCUGGUGCAGACCAGAGCCAUUCUCAACUACAUUGCCAGCAAAUACAACCUCUAUGGGAAAGACAUAAAGGAGAGAGCCCUGAUUGAUAUGUAUAUAGAAGGUAUAGCAGAUUUGGGUGAAAUGAUCCUCCUUCUGCCCGUAUGUCCACCUGAGGAAAAAGAUGCCAAGCUUGCCUUGAUCAAAGAGAAAAUAAAAAAUCGCUACUUCCCUGCCUUUGAAAAAGUCUUAAAGAGCCAUGGACAAGACUACCUUGUUGGCAACAAGCUGAGCCGGGCUGACAUUCAUCUGGUGGAACUUCUCUACUACGUCGAGGAGCUUGACUCCAGUCUUAUCUCCAGCUUCCCUCUGCUGAAGGUGACCCAUUUCACAGCCCAGAGAGGCAGCCCCACAUCUCCCAUCUUGGGAUCUUGUAUCUGGGCCCUGCGACUGACCAAGUUUUGCCCCAGUCUUCUCCAGGCCUUCAGUGCCCCAAGGUCUCCAAAAUGAGCUUCCAGGCUCCAAUUUUGAGGAAUGAAAACACUUUUGUUAUGGAAAGGAAAUCUGUGCUGCAUGCUACCCCACAAAGAGUAUUUUGCCCUUUAUUAUGGAAAGAACCCAGGGCCCAGCAUCUCUCCCCAUCCCUCUAUUUCAAUGUGGUUUCUGUUCCUGAGUUCUCUGUGAUGUCCUUUAUCCCAUAUGUGCCCACAAUGAGCCGGUCUGAGCAGAGCCCUUUCCAUCUGGUUUCCUCCCUGGGCUCCGGCUCCUGCUGUCUGACAUUGUGUUCCUCUCUGCACAGCUCUCCAGAACACUGGCCCCCCACACUGUAUCUCUCACUGAGAAAAGGUGGUCCCAUGGUUUGUCUUUAAUAUUUUCUAUAACUAUUCCCUUCCCAAAUAAUUUCCCCAUGUUUUCACUUCUGCUUAGAGACUCAUCUGUGUUGAUAUCUCACAGGCACAUUAUUUUUUCUUGUCUUAUACAAGAGUCACUAAUCUAUAGGAUUAGUGUGUAAGGAGAAAGAUAGAGAUGACUGAACUGAUUAAAACUUCAAGACAUCUUUGGGGAAAAUAAAGUGAGCUACAUGUCCUUCCCCUUAUCUUCAUUUCUCACUGGGUGUCUGUUUCUGCCUCCAUGCUUGUGCUGAUGGAGCAGACUCACUUGGUCUUUGCAGGAGGGGCUCAGAUUC